AGACAAGAUGGACACCGCGGAGGAAGGUAAGUCGGCGACGCGCGGCGCCCGAGCCCUUGCGUCGGCGCCCGGGUUCGUACCCCGGCCAGGUCCGCGGCGCUCGAGGUGGGCUGCUGGAUCGCGGCGGGGCGGACGCCUGGGCCGUUUGUCCACCCGCUGGGCCUCUGGGCCGGGGAGCGGAAGGUGACCCUCUGCGCGCCCCCCGCCGUUUCCCGCCCGCGCCGCCGAGGGGGGCGGGGACCCUGCCGGGCAGGGGCCGGGGCCGGGGUCGGGGCCUCGGGGCUACUGCAGGCCGGCGUGGCCUCCCUUGUCCCCGCCGUCGCGCGCUGGCCCAGAAAAGGGGGCCUCUGUCGCUGCCGUCCGGGGGCGUUUUCCGCACCCUUCCCCCACUGGGUUUUGUCUUUCUUUACGUCCUUCUGCCUAUUGCUCGCCAGGCCCUACCCCCUCGCGACAGAACUUCUUUGUUGACUUUGAAACUUCGCGAAAAAUACCCCGCCAGAUGACGGCCGAGUGGAGUGAGCUGACCCCUGUUGAAAAGCCUGGUCCUCGGCUUGCCUGCCGCUCGAGAAUCUGUUUACUAAACGGGGAGGCUCUUUUGUUGCGAUCCAUUUGGUUUUAAAUCCUUGACACCUAUAAGCAGGGUUCUGUUUGUUUUGUUUUGCGAUUGCUUGUGUUUUGGAUACGGUUACAUUGAACAAACUGACCCUUGUAAAAUGAAUACUUAAGAUAUAAACGUCCACACCUUAUGUCUCUUCAAACGCAUUUUCUUACCCACUGAAGGUAGUAGAUUAUUUUUAACCAGCUGUGUUUUUAAAUGAGUGGUGAGUUUAUAGAGGAAAUUACUAAAUUUUGCUUUUUUUGAUGUUCCGGUUAUCGUGCAAAUGCUUUUCUACUUUAGGUAUAUUUAUGGGGGUAUGAGCGUCUUUCAACCUUAUGGGUUGCGAUUUUGGCGAUUUUAAACGAAAAUGAAUUAUCAAACGCCGUCAUGGAGUGCAAUAAUGAGUGAAAAAAGUUUGAUAUUAUCUAUGUAAUGAGUUGAUAACGACUUAUUUUUUUUUAAAGAAGUCUUGCCUUUAAUAAAUACCUCAACUAUAACAUGUGGCACUUGAUGUACAUUCGCGUUCCAUCUUCGUAAAAAGCCUGUGGAAUAGACAUAUGUAGAGUGUGUCGGUCAGAAGGAACACCUGAGAAACCGCUUUAUCAUCCUUGUGUAUGUACUGGCAGUAUUAAGUUUAUCCAUCAAGAAUGCUUAGUUCAAUGGCUGAAACACAGUCGAAAAGAAUACUGUGAAUUAUGCAAGCACAGAUUUGCUUUUACACCAAUUUAUUCUCCAGAUAUGCCUUCACGGCUUCCAAUUCAAGACAUAUUUGCUGGACUGGUUACAAGUAUUGGCACUGCAAUACGAUAUUGGUUUCAUUAUACACUUGUGGCCUUUGCAUGGUUGGGAGUUGUUCCUCUUACAGCAUGCCGCAUCUACAAGUGCUUGUUUACUGGCUCCGUGAGCUCACUACUGACGCUGCCAUUAGAUAUGCUGUCAACGGAAAAUUUGUUGGCAGAUUGUUUGCAGGGUUGUUUUGUGGUGACGUGCACACUGUGUGCAUUCAUCAGCCUGGUGUGGUUGAGAGAGCAGAUAGUCCAUGGGGGAGCACCAAUUUGGUUGGAGCAUGCUGCCCCACCGUUCAAUGCUGCGGGGCAUCACCAAAAUGAGGCUCCAGCAGGAGGAAAUGGUGCAGAAAAUGUUGCUGCUGAUCAGCCUGCUAACCCACCAGCUGAGAACGCAGUGGUGGGGGAAAACCCUGAUGCCCAGGAUGACCAGGCAGAAGAGGAGGAGGAGGACAAUGAGGAGGAAGAUGACGCUGGUGUGGAGGAUGCGGCAGAUGCUAAUAACGGAGCCCAGGAUGACAUGAAUUGGAAUGCUUUAGAAUGGGACCGAGCUGCUGAAGAGCUUACAUGGGAAAGAAUGCUAGGACUUGAUGGAUCACUAGUUUUUCUGGAACAUGUCUUCUGGGUGGUAUCUUUAAAUACACUGUUCAUUCUUGUUUUUGCAUUUUGCCCUUACCAUAUUGGUCAUUUCUCCCUUGUUGGUUUGGGAUUUGAAGAACACGUCCAAGCAUCUCAUUUUGAAGGCCUAAUCACAACCAUAGUUGGGUAUAUACUUUUAGCAAUAACACUGAUAAUUUGUCAUGGCUUGGCAACUCUUGUGAAAUUUCAUAGAUCUCGUCGCUUACUGGGAGUCUGCUAUAUUGUUGUUAAGGUCUCUUUGUUAGUGGUGGUAGAAAUUGGAGUAUUCCCUCUCAUUUGUGGUUGGUGGCUGGAUAUCUGUUCCUUGGAAAUGUUUGAUGCUACUCUGAAAGAUCGAGAACUGAGCUUUCAGUCGGCUCCAGGUACUACCAUGUUUCUGCAUUGGCUAGUGGGAAUGGUAUAUGUCUUCUACUUUGCCUCCUUCAUUCUACUACUGAGAGAGGUACUUCGACCUGGUGUCCUGUGGUUUCUAAGGAAUUUGAAUGAUCCAGAUUUCAAUCCAGUACAGGAAAUGAUCCAUUUGCCAAUAUAUAGGCAUCUCCGAAGAUUUAUUUUGUCAGUGAUUGUCUUUGGCUCCAUUGUCCUCCUGAUGCUUUGGCUUCCUAUACGUAUAAUUAAGAGUGUGCUGCCUAAUUUUCUUCCAUACAAUGUCAUGCUCUACAGUGAUGCUCCAGUGAGUGAACUGUCCCUCGAGCUGCUUCUGCUUCAGGUUGUCUUGCCAGCAUUACUCGAACAGGGACACACGAGGCAGUGGCUGAAGGGGCUGGUGCGAGCGUGGACUGUGACCGCCGGAUACUUGCUGGAUCUUCAUUCUUAUUUAUUGGGAGACCAGGAAGAAAAUGAAAACAGUGCAAAUCAACAAGUUAACAAUAAUCAGCAUGCUCGAAAUAACAACGCUAUUCCUGUGGUGGGAGAAGGCCUUCAUGCAGCCCACCAAGCCAUACUCCAGCAGGGAGGGCCUGUUGGCUUUCAGCCUUACCGCCGACCUUUAAAUUUUCCACUCAGGAUAUUUCUGUUGAUUGUCUUCAUGUGUAUAACAUUACUGAUUGCCAGCCUCAUCUGCCUUACUUUACCAGUAUUUGCUGGCCGUUGGUUAAUGUCGUUUUGGACGGGGACUGCCAAAAUCCAUGAGCUCUACACAGCUGCUUGUGGUCUCUAUGUUUGCUGGCUAACCAUAAGGGCUGUGACGGUGAUGGUGGCAUGGAUGCCUCAGGGACGCAGAGUGAUCUUCCAGAAGGUUAAAGAGUGGUCUCUCAUGAUCAUGAAGACUUUGAUAGUUGCGGUGCUGUUGGCUGGAGUUGUCCCUCUCCUUCUGGGGCUCCUGUUUGAGCUGGUCAUUGUGGCUCCCCUGAGGGUUCCCUUGGAUCAGACUCCUCUUUUUUAUCCAUGGCAGGACUGGGCACUUGGAGUCCUGCAUGCCAAAAUCAUUGCAGCUAUAACAUUGAUGGGUCCUCAGUGGUGGUUGAAAACUGUAAUUGAACAGGUUUACGCAAAUGGCAUCCGGAACAUUGACCUUCACUAUAUUGUUCGUAAACUGGCAGCUCCCGUGAUCUCUGUGCUGUUGCUUUCCCUGUGUGUACCUUAUGUCAUAGCUUCUGGUGUUGUUCCUUUACUAGGUGUUACUGCGGAAAUGCAAAACUUAGUCCAUCGGCGGAUUUAUCCAUUUUUACUGAUGGUCGUGGUAUUGAUGGCAAUUUUGUCCUUCCAAGUCCGCCAGUUUAAGCGCCUUUAUGAACAUAUUAAAAAUGACAAGUACCUUGUGGGUCAACGACUCGUGAACUACGAACGGAAAUCUGGCAAACAAGGCUCAUCUCCACCACCUCCACAGUCAUCCCAAGAAUAAAGUAGUUGUCUCAACAACUUGACCUUCCCCUUUACAUGUCCUUUUUUGUGGACUUCUCUCUUUGGAGAUUUUUCCCAGUGAUCUCUCAGCGUUGUUUUUAAGUUAAAUGUAUUUGACUUGUGUUCUCAGCAUUCAGAGAGCAGCGGUGUAAGAUUCUGCUGUUCUCCCUGGAUCUUCUGACAUUACUGCUGUCUGAGAUUUGUAUAUGUGUAAAUACAAGUUCCUUGAUACCCUAAAACCUUGGAUUAAACAGAAUGUGCAUUGUACAUCUUUAAACAAAAUGUAUAUUAAUUUAUUAAAUCUAGUUGUCACUUUAUUUUGGACCUGCUGUGAUCUCGACAGGAAACGUGCCACAGAGCAGUAGUGCGCAGGCAAGACUUUUCAGUGACGCCUUGUGGAACGCAGUUCAUGAUGUCCUAGCAGCUCUCACUAAGGGAACUGUACAUUCUUUCUUUCUUGGCUAUUCAGACCUUACCAAGAACGUUAAAGGAAACAAGUAGAAAUCAGCAGUGGAGUGUCUGUGGUAAGAAAACAUGAACUUUAUGCUUCACUGUUAGUUGUUUGUGGAAGUUAUUUUGUAUAACACCAAAGCUGUUGUACAUUUCCUACUGCCUGAUUUUUUUCAUGUGUCUGUGUUUGUAAUAUUGUAUAGUAUCUUGUGCUAGGUGAGGAAAUUAUUUUUAAUUUUGAUAAUUUAAUAUUCCUAGUGUGAUCAGCAUUGGGAGUUGGGUUUCAGUGGGGCAUGUCUAUACUUAGAGAAAAAAAGUCCAAAUGAAGAUUUUCAUGAGUCAGCCCCCCCGCCCGCCCCCACCCCACACCCACAUCCUCUCUUUUCCACACACAACUAUCUGUUUAUUUUUUGUAGCAGUGGCCGAAAGUCCUGCAAGGUCAUAAAUCUUUCAGAGUGACAUCACCAACUGUACUGCAUCUUACUGGAUUUAGGACUUCUGAGAUGCUUGUGAAGUAUAGAUGUGGUUGUGGUCUUAGAUUGACAGCAUUAGAGAAGACUGGUUAGAACAUCUGGUCUCGCUGGUUAGUGCCUCGUUGGCUGAGGACUAGGUGUGCAUUUCUCCUAGCUUUUCAUCAGGAAAUCCCAAAGUUUCCAAAGCUUUUUGUUUACAGAAUAAAACUUCAAAUAAAACCAAUUCAUUAUUUGUCCAGAAGGAAGCUUGGCUGAGCUGGCCUUUUAACAUAGGAAUGUAUUUCGUUGGAAACAUUCUGAAAAAUCUCAGAGAACUGAACCCUUACAAACUUUGUUUUCCCUCAUAACCAAAGCUUCAGGUUAGAAGUUUAGAAAAAUAGAAUGGUUGGGUACAUGAUCUAAAUGUUUAAUGCUAAAGGUAUAUCGUAAGGGUAGUGUUUGUUUUUGAACGAUAAUUUAGAAGUUCUCAUAGAAAGCGUAUAACAUAGGUCUUCAGAAACUAUAAAAGAAUUUUCAUAUAGUAUUAAAAUCCAUAGACUAAAAUCUGAGAAUUUUUUAACAUAUGCAAGUCAGCCAAACAUAAGCUACCAAAAUAAAGAGCAAUGUGUUCUGGCUGUUUUAUACUUCAACAAUUUUUUCCCUAAGUGGUAAGCAAUUACUUUAAAACAUAUUUUUAAAAACAUCGGUAUCGGGAGCUGCGGUGGCUCCGGCCGGUUGUCCUGGCACACAAGGAGGCGAGGCUAUGCGUUCGAGGCCAACCUAGGCAAAAUUGGAAAAAAAAAAAAAAAUCAGUAUCAGAAAUAAUGCUUGACAUAGGAUUCAGUGUUAUACUCUUUGGCACUUUAGAGCAGCCUUUUCUCUCAUUUGAAAUAAGGUCUUUGUUAGCCCUACCUUUACUCAGAAAUUUAGUCCUACUAUAAAAAAUUAGGAUUUUAAAAUAUAAUGCUGCCUGUCAUAGUGUAUUUCUAAAUUGCUCUCUUUGGGAGAAAAACAUUAUUAUUGAAUUGAGCAUAUAACUAUAUAACUAUAUAACUAUAUAUAUAUAUAUAUAUAUAUAUAUAUAUAUAUAUAUAUAUAUAUAUAUAUAUAUAUUUUUUUUUUUUUUUUUUUUUUUUUUUUUUUGCCCCCGAGACAGAGUCUUACUCUGUUGCCCAGGCUGGAGUGCAGUGGCACGAUCCUGGUUCACUGCACCCUCUGCCUCCCAGGUUCAAGCGAUUCUCCUGCCUCAGCCUCCCAAGUAGCUGGUACUACAGGUGCGUGCCACCACACCUGGCUUAUUUUAGUUAUUUUAGUAGAGAUAGGGUUUCACCAUGUUGGCCAGGCUGGUCUCGGAACUCCUGACUGCAGGUGAUCCGUCCUCCUUGGGCUCCCAAAGUGCUGGGAUUAUAGGUGUGAGCCCCCACGCCUGGCCAACUUGAUUAUAUUAAUUUUGGGUUUUUUGUUUUGUUUUGUUUUGUUUUUUAAUUUUUCAAAGAAUUUGUGGAUCUUGGUAUAAAGUCAUUGGAACAUAUCUGUUUUAACAGCAAGAGAUCCUAGGCAGAUACUUCAAAAGGUUAAAAAUUCUUAAUCCUACAGAAUUUUAAAUGAAUCUUAUCAAUGUUUUGUAAACAAACAAUAUGAAUGGCCAAAAAAUUGCCCUCCAUUUUACUGGCAGGUAAUUUAUAUUGUCUUACUUAAGAAUUCUCCCCUAGUUUUUCAAUUGUACUUUAUCGUGUUGUUUUCAAUGAGAUAAGUAUUUUCAUAGGGAAAGCAUUUUCCAGCAUAAUAUUUGCUUGGGUAGCAUCCGGGUUUUAGUAUUUAACCAAGAGCCUUUUAAAUAUUGAAAACCCAUAGUUCAGAAAAUGUUAGUAUUGCUGCCCUUCUUCACAUAAAUUUUUUUUUAAAUUAUACUAUUAUUUUGCUUAAUUUUAUAUUGGGUUAAAACAACCUUCAAGAAGGUUAACUAGGAAAGAAGACCUUUUUGUUUUAUUUUUACUAUUUAUAUAUAGAAGACAAAUCAGCAUUUGGUGAUAGUUUUACAUGACCAGUUAUCAAACGGUCAUAGUAUGAAGUGUGCAGUUGUUCAUUAUUAGUAAAUUAUGUUUGAUUUUUAAACUAUUUAGUACUAAUAGUUGAGAUGAAAACUGAAGAAAAAUGCCAAUGUGACGUUUGUGUAUAGCUAGCCUUAAAAAACUUCCCAUGUUUUUAGGUGACUUUUUUCCCCCUCUUAGUACUCUGGAGAAACAAUGAAGAUGGGCCAUCUCAAUUCCAGAUGUAAACAAAAAGUAAUUUUUAUUUCAACAUUUAAUGUAACUGCUAUUAUUGUGGAUUCUUGUCUUGUGUAUUUUCUUUCCCUUAUUCAAGUAAUAUAGAAUAACUUUCCUUAAAAUGAUUUGAUCCAAGAUACGUCAUUUCUGUAUUGGCAAAAUGCCACUAUUAAAGUGUAAUUCUUGAAUUUAGGUUGAAUUGAUGACUUUUUAAAACAAAACAAACACUGGACAGUUCUACAUUGUAUUGCGUUUGCGAAUGUGCGUGAACACACGCACACGUGCAGGAGAAUGUAGUGCCAUAAGAACACUGGCGCUUUUUAAAACUUUCCAAGCUAGCUACUUAUUUUCAUUUUCAGGGUUGAGUACUCUAAGCUCUCUACUUACUGUGAGAAGUUUUCUACAUUGUAAAAUUAAAAGAUUAUAUUUAAAAUACUUCUUUAGGAUGUUAUUCAGCCAUCAAAAAAAAACCCAACUAAAAUGUCUUACCAGUAAAGUAUUAUUAAAAGCCUCAUUUGUGGAGAUUCGCUGACUUCCUUGGUUAAGCUGUCUUGUAUUUACUUAAUUUGUCCCCUCAACCAGGUGUUUUCUUUUCAGCCUGUUACUGUCCUGUGCCAUUUUUAAAAAUAGCCAUCAUGAGUAAGGGCUUCUUUAAAAUAAUCCCUGACAAUAUCUUUGGCAUUAAUACGACAUAAAGACAAGACAGUAUAUGUAUGUUUUCAUUCCUGUUUUGUACGAGUGCCUCAUUUUGUAGUCAUGAAAGUAACAUAGUACCUUAAAUAAAAAUGUAAUGACUAAUCUAAGGUCUAGGAAUAACUAUUGUAGAAGCUAAGUAGAACACUUAGUUUGGGGUGUCAAUUUUCUAUCAACGCAAACACCUUAGGGUACCCAGACCAAUUUUAUGUAUAUAUAUUCUGAAAUGCUCCCUUUUUAAUGUGGUCAUUUGUUGCCUUCUAAGUUGAGAGGACAAAACUGAAUAAAGUGAAUGUUAAUUGUAGUCUAGUUUUUUUGUUUGUUUUUGUGUUAUUGCAAGAUUGCUUUAAGAUUGCAGAAAUAUGCAUUAUUAGCCAGCAUAGAUAAUCCAGAUGUUAUAAUAGGAAGGAAAAACAACUCCAGUUAAAUGUGACUGUGGCGACUCCCUUUUAUGUAUACAUUUAAAUGCAUAGUUGCAGAGGACACAUCCCUCCCCUUCUGUCUCCCUAACUUGAACUGUAGACCGUCCUCACUGGGAAGAGUAAGGCCCCACAUUUUGUGCAAUAGCAAGCUACUGCCCACUUCUGCAUGUCUGCUACGAGAUCAGAAAGUCAGUUUCACUAAGGUUGUCUUUUAGCUGAAUACUUAGAGUAAAACCAAUCAAAUCCAUUGUACAUACCUGACCAUAUGUCCCAGAUAAAAAGGAAAGACUUGCGUGAUGUUUUUUUCCUUCUGAGUGCCCUGAGGAGAUCCUUUUGCUUCAGACUAUUUCUAAUUUUUCUUUGUUUAUAGGUUCAGAAUUUUUUCCAUGAUUGUUUUCCCCCAAACAAGUGCAUUUUUAAUUACUUUAAAUGCAGGGGUGAUAGAGGAAAUGCUAUUCGAACCAUAGACAUCUUUAAUCUGUGAAGCUGAAAUUUUUCAGCAAAGGAAAUUGCAUGGUCAAGUUCAGAAACUGGCCAUUAAUUUCCCCCUUCCGCUCCACAGUUCAUAGCUACUCUUGUUGCAAACAUGUAGUGAUAAGGAGAACUAACGUAUCAAGGGGCUGAGAGGGUAACGUUCCCCUCCUCCUCCAUGUUUUUAUUUUGGUGUCUGUUUUGUUUCUAGCACUGUAUUUAGUACUGUAGUUGAAUGAGGUAUGAUGUCUCCCUUCAAGGAACUCAGAAUGGAACAGAAGCAUGAGCAAAAGAUUGUAUUACAGAGGUAUGAAUAAAAUGCCAUGGGGAACACAGAGAAAGGUUCACCCGGGAGAGAUGGCCUAGCCACUUCCUUAGUGACUGUUUGGUAUAUGUAGGUCCCCCUGCCAUUACUCUUUCAGCCUUCUGCAAUCUAGUUCUACUUAGUCACACACUUCUCUAAGACCACUCAUACGUAAACACUACGUAGAGGCCCCUUUUUGCCUCAUUUUACAUUGUUUAGUUAUCAUUUUGAAACUUUUCUUCACAUAUGUAACAGUGCCGGAGUUUUUCUGCUUCUCUGUGUUUGUUCAGUAACUCUUCUUUAGGAUACACCUAAAGAUGAGAAGCUUCAUACCCAGUACUCCUCUUCAUUCACUCAUAUGUUUUUGGGAUCAGUCCCUUCUGCUGGCUGUGCAUUGGUCUAAUGGAACAGAAUAGAGUCCAGAAAUAACCCAACAUGUAUGUGGACAACUGGUUUUUGACAGAGGUGCAAAGGUCUUGAAAAAAUGAUGCUGGAAUAAUUGGGCAUCAGAUGCAAAAUUAAAAACAAAUUGAUCCAUAUCUUAACACUGGCAAAGAUUAAAGUCCAAAUGGAUUAUAGUUCCCCAAAACUGUAUAAUUUCUAGAAGACAACAAGGAAAACGUGUUCAGCCUUGGGUUAGGAAAAGAUUUCUUAAAUCCAACACCAAAAGCACAAUCCAUGAAGGAAAAAUCGAUAAAUUGUACUUUAUCAAAAUUGAGAACUUCUCUUUGAAAGGUACCAUAAGGAGAACAAAAAGACAAGCUGUAGAGUGGCAGAAAAAUAUUUGCAAAACAUUUCUGAUAAAUGAGUUGCAUCUAGAUUACAUAAAGAAGUCUCAAAACUGAACAAGUAAACCCAUUGUUUACUUAAUCGCUGUUUCUCCUGAGCUUGCUGCCUCUGCCCCUGCUCUCUCUCCUUUUCCAUUUGUUUUCAACAUUGAAUCCAGAAUGUUCUUCUUGAGAUCCAAGUCAGAUCACACCAACCCUCAGAACUCUCCAAUAGACGACCAUGGCACUCAAAAGUCCACAAUAGCCUUCAAUGCUGGGCAAAACAUGAAGCACCCCUUUUCUCCCUUCUCUGACCCCAUCACCUCUGUGUUCACCCUGCUCCUGCCGUCCUCCCUGCCUCCAAAACAGGUCAGGCCUUCGUGCCUUUGCACUUACUAUUUGCAAUACCCAAAUGUUCUUCAGGCUCUUUAGCCUCUUCAUUUCUUUCCUGAAGUGUCAUUCUCACUGAGGCUUAUCUAAAGCUGCAGCUACUGGGGCAUUCCUGUCUCAUCUCCCUGCUGUAUUUUGUACUCCCGGCUCUCUUUUGUACUUUUAAACAUACUAUAUGGUUUACCUUUGUUGUUUAUAUUUGCAUGUUGUUUCCCACUUGAAUGUAAGCUCCAAAGAUUUUAUUUUUUUAAACUGAAUUAUUACUGUAUUCCCAGAACAAUUCCCUGGCAAAUAUUUGGUACUCAAUAGUAAUGCUAAGUUAGUAAAUAAAUGAUGAAUUUAGAAUCAAAAUAAUGUGUCUAUGGCCAAAAUAAAACCUGAAAUCCCUGUCCUAUUUCCCAGAGGUAACUGCUGUUAAUAGUUUAGUUGUGUGCUUCCAGACAUACCUUCACAGAAUCAUUUAUCACAAUAAAGGUGUCAUACUAUGCA